GUCUCCAGCUCCCGCUAGACCUUGGGACCCGCCUCUGCUUUUCCGCGUUCUCCAACUCGGGAAUCCCCGGUGACUUUGUCGCAGCCUCCGUUACCCUGUGAUCUGCAAGUCCUGGGAGACGCACAGCUAAGAUGCCCGGACAUCCUGGAAGCUGGGAAAUGAGAUGGGGUUUCACCAUGUUGGCCAGGCUGAUCUCGAACUCCAGACCUCAGGUCAUACGCCCGCCUCAGCCUCCCAAAAGUCCUGGGAUUACAGGCGUGAGCCACCGCGCCCGGCCUCUUAGGAACAUUUCUGAAUCUCACACUCGGAGGCUGUCAAAAGUUGGAUAAUUGACUUUCAUAUGCGGGCCUGGUCCACAGGUGGGUUGGUUACUCUCAGACCAAGAUUCAGUACACAUGUGAGGCUGUGACUGCACUGAAAAGCACAGUCCGCAGACAAAAUUGUGGCUCUCUUGCAAUACCGUCAACCAUUGAGAUUGUGACUCACGUACUUAGACAGACCCAACAUACAGGAGGUGUUGACCCUCAUACCUGGAACCUGGACAUGUGUGGAAUUUCUAAUCUCAUUCCUGGACUUUCCUGCAGGUGAUGUGACUCUUCUUCAGCCUGCACCCUGCCAAAAGAGGAUUGUGAUGUAUCACUGGACCCAGCACCUAGAUGACGUAACUCUCAUCUUUUGCCUGGACCUUGCAUAUUUUGGGUGUGAUUGUGACACAUACCUCUGCUCAGAAUGUGAGCGAUUUGACUCUCCUGCCUGGGCCCAGUACACAGAUGGGAUUGUGACAUAUCGCUGGACCCAGCAUGUAGAUCAUGUGACCCUAUACUCUUGCCUUGGUGCUGUCGCAGAGGGCAUUGUGACAUAUCACUGGUCCCUGCACCCAGGUAAUGUGUUUCUCCUUUCUGUGCCCUGCCCAAAUGGGCUAUUGUAACAUAUUACUGGAUCUAACACCCAGAUGAUAUGAAUCUCCUACCUAGACCCUGGCUUCAGGGGACAUUUUGCCAUAUUUCUGGACCCAUCUAUUUAAUGUUACUCUUCACCUUUACAUGGGCUUUUCCCUAGGAGACGUUGUAACAUAUCUGUGCCAAGCACCUACAUGAUCUCACUCUUCUCUCCUGCCUGGGCCCUGACCACAGAAGAGGGGGUGACGUAUCACUAGGCCCUGACCACAGGUUAUGUGAUUUUUCUGCCUGGUCCCUGUCCAGAGAGGACAUUAUGACAUUUGCCUGGGCCCAUAAACUAGAUUAUAUGACUCUCCUUUUGUCUCUGAAACUUGUCCACAGUGGAGAUUUUGACAUACCACUUUUCUCAGGAUCUACAUAAUCUGAAUUUUGUUCCAUGCCUCAGUCUUGCCCACUGGGGUGAUUGUGCCAUAUAACUAGUCUCAAUUCCUAGGUUAUGUGACUCUUCUUUAUGAGCCUUACCCACAUAGGGCAUUUUGACAUAUCUCUGGAGCCCUCUCUUAGAUGAGGUGACUGUGCUGCACGGUCCCCUUUUUUUCAGAAAAUAUUGUGCCAUAUUUUUUGACCUAGUAACAAGGUGAUGUGACCCUCGUCUACUGCUUGGUUUCUGCCCAAGGCGGGAUUGUGAUUUUUUUAUUUUAUUGUUUUUUUUUUUUUUUGAGAUGGAGUCUCACUUUGUUGCCAGGCUGGAGUGCAGUGGCACGAUCUCAGCUCACUGCAACCUCUGCCUCCCGGGUUCAAGCUAUUCUUCUGCCUCAGCCUCCCAAGUAGCUGGGGCUACAGGCAUGCACCACCAUACCUAGCUAAUUUUUGUAUUUUUAUUAGAGACAGGAUUUCACCACGUUGUCCAGGAUGCUCUCGUUCUCUUGACCUGGUGAACCACCAGCCUCUGCCUCCCAAAGUGCUGAGAUUACAGGUGUGAGCCACCAUGCCUGGCCAGGGAUUGUGAUUUUUCACUGGGCCUAGCACCUUGGUGAUGUGACUCUCCUCUCCUACUACAGGUUUCAGUUAGAAAAGGAGAGUCACGUCACUUAGGUGAUAAACAGAAAGAUAAUGUCAUAAUUCUCCUAUUAGCAGGGCCCAUGCAGGAGAGUCACAUCACCUAGUUGUUGGACCCUGCCAUAUUUCAAUAUACACAAUUUGUUUCACCUAGGUAUUGGUGAAUUGUGUAUUGUAUAUAUUAAAAUAUGGCUAGUCCAACACCUAGGUGAUGGGACUCUCUUCACCUGCUAAUAGAGGAAUUAUGACAUGUCAUUUGUUUAUCACCUAAGUGAUGUAACUUCUACCUGAACCCUGUAAAAGGGGAGGAUUGUGACAUAUCACUGGACUCUGUAUCUAGGUGAUAUCACUCUCUUUAACCUGGGCCCCUUGUAUUGUGGGUAUUAUGACACAUCAGUGGCUCAAACCAAAUGGGUAAAGAGCUCUUGCCUGGGCCCUGUCUGUGGGAAGCACCUUGUGACAUAUCUGUGCAUCCAUUACUUUGGAGGUGUGACUCUCCUCUUCCAUCUGCACCAUGCCCAGAGAAAGAUUGUGUUGCAUCUCUGGGUUCAGCAACCAGGUGCUGUGUUUCUUGUGCCCAGGCCUUGCCUGCAGAGAGAAUUGUGACAUAGCUGGGUCCAGUACCAAGUAACGUGACUUUGUUGUCUGUGCCUUGCUUUCGAGAAGGAAUUGUAACAUAACCCUGGACAGGCAACCAGGUAAUAUGACUCUCCUGCCUGGUCCUUGUCCUGAAAAAUUGUGACAUAUUUCCGACUCAGCAUGCAGGUGAUGUUACUCUCCCAUUUACUUUCUACUCACAGGUUAGAUUGUGACAUACACUUUAGCCCAGUUCACAGUUGCGAUGAUGAUACUCAUACCACAAACCAGUCCAUAGCAGAGAUACUGGUGCUGGUAGCUAGACUUAGAGAAACAGGUAAAGUCCUGGAUUACCAUUCUUUCACAUUUUGUAUAAAGUCUUUGGACGGUACAGAGAGUGUUAUCAUAGGGCCAAGCACACAGGUGAGACUGUUUCUCAAAUGCACAACCUACCAAAUGUUAGCAUUGUCACCCUCACACGAAUUUCACACGUGAAUGGAGUCCACAGUAAAAAUUGUGACUGUCAUAUGUAAUCAUGUGACAACAGUUAAGAUGGUGACUCAUUUCUAAACCUAGCUCAUAGGCAGGUGAGAACUCUUUUCUCUAGACCCAGCCAAUUGGAGAGAUGUUGACUCUAAUGCAUGAGCCUAGGUCCACAGGUAUGAUUAUGAGUUUGUAUUAGAAAAAAAAGUCUCAGAGCAAAUUGUGACCAUCAUGGAUAUUGUAUAAAGCCCUCAGGUAGUAUAGAGAGUUCUAUAACAGGGCCUAGCACCCAGGUGACAUUGUGACACUCGUAUGCAAACCCAGCCAACAGUGAAAAUUGACAACUUUCCACAUGAACACAGCUCACUGUUGAAGUUCUGAAUCUCACACCUGGAGGUGGUUGGAAAAUUGACUCUCAAACGUGGAUUCGGUUCACACGUGGGCUGGUGACUCUCAAACCAAGAUUCAGCAUACCUGUGAGGCUGUGACUCCACUAAGGGGACACAGUCCACGGCAAAGAUUGAGGCUCUCAUGGAUGUAUCCAGUCCACCGUUGAGAUUGUGACUUGUGUACUUGGACUCAACAUACAACAUGUGUUGACUCUAAUACUAAGAAAUGGGAUGUGUGGGAUUGUUCAUUCCUACAUUUUUUUGUGACUGUGAUUGUAACAUACACCUUUGCCCAGCACCUGAGUGAUUUGACUCUCCUGCCUGGUGCCUAGUGCACAGAUCGGAUUGUGACACAUUGCUGAAUCCAACAUCUAGGUGGUGUGACUCUGUACUUUUGCCUCAGCACUGCCCACAGGGGGGCAUUGUGACAUAUCACUGGACCCCACACCCUGGUUAUGUGACUCUUCUGCCUGUGCCCUAUCUUCAUGGGCCAUUGUGACAUUGCUAUGUGCAACAUCCAGGUGAUGUAACUUUCCUUGCUGGAUCCUGCUUGCAGGAAGCAUUAUAAUCUAUCUGCAUCCAUCACCCAAGUAAUGUGACUCUCUUUCUACCAGGUUGCUGCUUACAGAAAGAAUUGUUACCUAUCACUGGGCCAGCACCUAGCUGUUGUGAUGCUUCUUUUUCUACCUACAUUCAGCUCACAAUGUAGAUUUUGACAUACUGCUGGGCUAAACACCAAAAAUGAAGUUACGUUUUUCCUCAGCACUUUCCUCAUCAGGCAUUGUGACAUAUUGUUUGGCCCAGAACUAAGGUAAUGUGAGCCUCCUGCCUGAACCCUGCCCAUAGUGGGCAUAGUGACAUAUUUGUGAACCCAUCAUCCAUAUAAUGUGACUUUCUUACUUGGCUUUUCCCUAUAGGAGAGAUUGUGACAUAUAUUUGAGCCCAGAAACCAAAUAAUUUGACCCUUCUUUCCUGCUAUGGCCAUGCUCCCAUAAAAGAGAGUGACUUAUUGCUGCGAUUAGCACACAGGCUAUGUGAUUCUUCUGCCUGGUUCCUCUCCACAGGAGUUACUUUGACAUAUCUCUGGGCCCAUUACUUAGAUGAUGUGACUCCUCUUAUUCCUGGGAUGUGUUCACAGUUUGGACUGUAACAUAUCGCUUAGUCAAGCACUUAUGUGAUGUGACUCUUCUCUCAUGUUUUGGCCUUGUCCACUGGGGUGCUUGUGAUAUGUAGCUGGGCCCAGCUCUUAGGUUAUGUGAUCUCUUUUUUUUUUUUUUUUUUUUUUUUUGCCUGAUCUCUGCAUACAUUUUGUAUUGUGAUAUAUAUGGCUGGGUCCAACACCUAGGUAUUAUGAGUCUCCUGAAUGGGCUCUGUUCAGAAAGGUAUUAUGACAUAUUCUUUUUUCUUCAUCACUUAAAUGUUGUGACUCUCCUUUUUUGACUAGAACCUGCUACAAAGGAUAAUUGUGAAAUAUCACUGGACCCAGCACCUAGGUGAUGUGACUCUCCUUUUUGCCUGGGUCUCACAUAAUUUGGGUAUUGUGAUAUAUUGCUGAGACCAACAUCUAGGGGGUGGGAAGCUCCUUUCUUGACCCUAACCACAGGAGCUUUGUGACAUAUCUCUGCAUCCAUGAUCUAAAUAUGUGAUUCUGUGUUUCUGCCUGCACCCUGCUAACAGAGAAGAUUACGACAAAUUUCUAAGUGCAGUGUAUCUUGUUUAUCUUGUGCUGACCUCCUAUCUCAUCCUGUGACUAAGAAUGCCUAACCUGGGGAGGCAGCCAAGUAGGUUUCAGCAUAUUUCACACAGCUGCUAUUCAAGAUUGAGUUGCUCUGGUUUGAAUGCCUCCAACAUUAAGAUCCACUAUAAAAUUAUGAAAAAAGUCUAGAGUAAAUGAGAAUUAAAUUAGGAUGGGCUAUUCUACCCUGGGUGCGGUGGCUUACUCCUGUAAUCCCAGCACGUUGGGAGGCCAAGGCGGGCGAAUCACCUGAGGUCAGGAGUUUGAGACCAGCCUGGCCAACAUGGGGAAACCCCGUCUCUACUAAAAAUACAAAAAUUAGCCAGGUGUGGUAGCGCACAUCUGUAAUCCCAGCUACUCGGGAGGCUGAGGCAGGGGAAUUGCUUGAACCCAGGAGGCGGAGGUUGCAGUGAGCUGAGAUUGCACCACUGCACUCCAGCCUGGGUAAUAGAGCGAGACUGUAUCUCCAAAAAAAAAAAAAAAAAUUUAGAAUGGGCUAUUCUGAAAGAUGUAGCAAUAAUUAUAUUUGUGUUUAUGAGUUUUUUUUAUUAACCUCUACACUUGAUAAUGAAAGAGGUUUCCACUGCUAAAGGAAAAUAAAUCUCUUGAUGCCAAAAUUACUAAGCCACUAGAAAAGUCAAGUUGAGAACUAUGUCAGGCAAAUCUGCCUCCCAUUUUAUUUCUAAAUAAGAUAGCUACAAAGAUAAAAAAGCUACAUACUUUCUUUACAAUUAGCCAACAAGGAAAUUCCUUGAGAACCAAAGACAGACAGAACUCAGAGUCAUUUCUCUGAGCCUCGCCUGAGACAAAUGCACAUCUGAUUGCUUCCUCUGCACUGCUGUUAAUUUAGAUAUGCAGGUUCACUGAGCCAGACUAAAUUGUAUUCAGUUGAAUGCUUAUCAAGGACUCAAGAAUCCAGACUUUUAUCUCUUAUUUACUUAUGACCUGGAAGCCCUCACCUCAAGUUGUCCUGCAUUACUGGAUCAAACCAAGAAAGAGAGAGAGGAAGGAGGAGGUGGAGAAGGAAAAAGGGACCAUUGACAUUUAUGGAUGUGGCCAUAGAAUUCUGUCUGGAGGAGUGGCAAUGCCUGGACAUUGCACAGCAGAAUUUAUAUAGGAAUGUGAUGUUAGAGAACUACAGAAACCUGGUCUUCCUGGGUAUUGCUGUCUCUAAGCCAGACCUGAUCACCUGUCUGGAGCAAGAAAAAGAGCCUUGGGAGCCUAUGAGGAGACAUGAAAUGGUAGCCAAACCCCCAGUUAUGUGUUCUCAUUUUACCCAAGACUUUUGGCCAGAGCAGCAUAUAAAAGAUCCUUUCCAAAAAGCGACACUGAGAAGAUAUAAAAACUGUGAACAUAAAAAUGUACAUUUAAAAAAAGACCAUAAAAGUGUGGAUGAGUGUAAGGUGCACAGAGGAGGUUAUAAUGGAUUUAACCAAUGUUUGCCAGCUACCCAGAGCAAAAUAUUUCUAUUUGAUAAAUGUGUGAAAGCCUUUCAUAAAUUUUCAAAUUCAAACAGACAUAAGAUAAGCCAUACUGAAAAAAAACUUUUCAAAUGCAAAGAAUGUGGCAAAUCAUUUUGCAUGCUUCCACAUCUAGCUCAACAUAAAAUAAUUCAUACCAGAGUGAAUUUCUGCAAAUGUGAAAAAUGUGGAAAAGCUUUUAACUGCCCUUCAAUCAUCACUAAACAUAAGAGAAUUAAUACUGGAGAGAAACCCUACACAUGUGAAGAAUGUGGCAAAGUCUUUAAUUGGUCCUCACGCCUUACUACACAUAAAAAAAAUUAUACUAGAUACAAACUCUACAAAUGUGAAGAAUGUGGCAAAGCUUUUAACAAGUCCUCAAUCCUUACUACCCAUAAGAUAAUUCGCACUGGAGAGAAAUUCUACAAAUGUAAAGAAUGUGCCAAAGCUUUUAACCAAUCCUCAAACCUUACUGAACAUAAGAAAAUUCAUCCUGGAGAGAAACCUUACAAAUGUGAAGAAUGUGGCAAAGCCUUUAACUGGCCCUCAACUCUUACUAAACAUAAGAGAAUUCAUACUGGAGAGAAACCCUACACAUGUGAAGAAUGUGGCAAAGCCUUUAACCAGUUCUCAAACCUUACUACACAUAAGAGAAUCCAUACUGCAGAGAAAUUCUAUAAAUGUACAGAAUGUGGUGAAGCUUUUAGCCGGUCCUCAAACCUUACUAAACAUAAGAAAAUUCAUACUGAAAAGAAACCCUACAAAUGUGAAGAAUGUGGCAAAGCUUUUAAGUGGUCCUCAAAGCUUACUGAACAUAAGUUAACUCAUACUGGAGAGAAACCCUACAAAUGUGAAGAAUGUGGCAAAGCCUUUAACUGGCCCUCAACCCUUACUAAACAUAACAGAAUUCAUACUGGAGAGAAACCCUACAAAUGUGAAGUAUGUGGCAAAGCCUUUAACCAGUUCUCAAACCUUACUACACAUAAGAGAAUUCAUACUGCAGAAAAACCGUACAAAUGUGAAGAAUGUGGCAAAGCUUUUAGCCGGUCCUCAAACCUUACUAAACAUAAGAAAAUUCACAUUGAAAAGAAACCCUACAAAUGUGAAGAAUGUGGCAAAGCUUUUAAGUGGUCCUCAAAGCUUACUGAACAUAAGAUAACUCAUACUGGAGAGAAACCCUACAAAUGUGAAGAAUGUGGCAAAGCUUUUAACCAUUUCUCAAUCCUUACCAAACAUAAGAGGAUUCAUACUGGAGAGAAACCCUACAAGUGUGAAGAAUGUGGCAAAGCUUUUACCCAAUCCUCAAACCUUACUACACAUAAGAAAAUUCAUACUGGAGAGAAAUUCUACAAAUGUGAAGAAUGUGGCAAAGCUUUUACCCAAUCUUCAAACCUUACUACACAUAAAAAAAUUCAUACUGGAGGAAAACCCUACAAAUGUGAAGAAUGUGGCAAAGCUUUUAACCAGUUCUCAACUCUUACUAAACAUAAGAUAAUUCACACUGAGGAGAAACCCUACAAAUGUGAAGAAUGUGGCAAAGCCUUUAAGUGGUCCUCAACCCUUACUAAACAUAAGAUAAUUCAUACUGGAGAGAAACCCUACAAAUGUGAAGAAUGUGGCAAAGCUUUUAAACUGUCCUCAACCCUUUCUACACAUAAGAUUAUUCAUACUGGAGAGAAACCCUACAAAUGUGAAAAAUGUGGCAAAGCUUUUAACCGAUCCUCAAACCUUAUUGAACAUAAGAAAAUUCAUACUGGAGAGCAACCCUACAAAUGUGAAGAAUGUGGCAAAGCAUUUAACUAUUCCUCACACCUUAAUACACAUAAGAGAAUUCAUACUAAAGAGCAACCCUACAAAUGUAAAGAAUGUGGCAAAGCUUUCAACCAAUAUUCAAACCUUACUACACAUAACAAAAUUCAUACUGGAGAGAAACUCUACAAACCUGAAGAUGUGACAGUGAUUUUGACAACACCUCAAACUUUUUCAAACAUAAAAUAAAUUAUACUGGUGAGAAAUUCUAGAAAUGUAAAGAAUGUGAUAAAGGCUUUACAUGGUUGUCACACUUGAUUGUAGGUAAGAUAAUUUACAUUGGAGUAAACUUCUACAAGUGUGAAGAAUGUGGCAAAACUUUUAAUUAAUGCUCGUACCUUAUUGCACAGGAAAGAAUUUUUACUUGGAAAAAGGUAUAUACACAAAGAAUGUGGAAAAGCCAUUAAUAUGUGCUCAUAUCUUACUCAACAUCAGAGAGUCUGUACUUAAUAAAACCAUUAUAGAUGCAACUAGUGUCAAAAGAUCUUUCAGAAAAUAAAAGCCUUUAAAGUGAAGAAGAUAAUUCAUUCUGAAGACAAACAUUACAAAUAUUAAGAGGGUUGUAGUACCAUUACUUGCAUCACAGAUCUUAUUGUACACAUUUUGUACUAAAGAAAACCCUGAAGCAGUUGCUCAAAUACUGUUCAACAUCAGAAAAUUUAUAUUGGAAAAAACCCCUGGAAAAUGUAAUAAAUUUGUAAAAACAGUUUUGAAAAACUACAGCUUAUAAAACAUGAGGGUCUAUAAUGCUUGGUUGAUAGUACAAAGUUUAUUCAACAUCAGGGAAUUUAUAUUGGAGAAAAACCCUACAAAUGUAAUCAGUUUGGAAAAACAUUUUUAAAAAAACCACAGCAUAGAAAACACCACAGGGUUCAUACUAAAAUAUGUUUUUGCAGAUGCAGUAAAAAUGAAAAAAAUUUAAUCCGAAAUUAAGUUUAUGUAAAUAUCUGAGAAUUCACAGUAGAAAUAUCUAAGGCGCGGACACUUCAGACAUUACACUAAAUCAGUGCUAAGUACAGAAAACAACACAAAAUAAAACUUGGUGGAUAAAUUAUUUGUAUAUAACAUUAAAAGAAGUAGAAGAUUUUCAGUUAUAAUUACAAUUAAAGUAUACUUUUAUCUUGAAAAAAUUACUGAUUUUUAAAUUAGUGAAUAAUGAUGUAAUUAAACUCUCAAAUAACUUUAUGCUCUUUUUUCAUUCCUGCUAUAUUCACAUGUGAAAGCAUGUGACCAAUUGUUGCUGCACCAAAGAUAUGAGAGAUUCUUUUAUUAGGUGGGCAUUAUUUAAAACAUUUUUUAUGGAACAGUAAGGAUAUUAAAGUGUAAGAUGCAGCCAGGCAUGGUGGCUCAUGCCUAUAAUCCCAGCACUUUGGGAGGCUGAGGCCGGUGGAUCACCUGAGGUCAGGAGUUUGAGACCAGCCUGACCAACAUGGUGAAACCCUGUCUUUACUAAAAAUACAAAAAUUUACCAGGCACCUAUAAUCCCAGCUACUUCAAAGGCUGAAGCAGGAGAAUCACUUGAACCUGGAAAGUGGAGGUCUCAGUGAGCCGAAAUCAUACCAUUGCACUCCAACCUGGGCAACAAAAGUCAAACUCCAUCUCAAAAAGAAAAAAAAAAAAAAAAAAGAUGCGUGAUGAAAAUGUAACUGGAGAGGCUCUUUGUGGUUAACUUAUAAAGGAGUGAUGCAGGAGAUAGGUUUUCAGAGUAAUAUUCUUCUGCAUUAUAGUGACAAAAGUUUUUUAUUUUAGUUAAAAUUGGUUAAAUUAGUAAGUCAUUUUACUUAUUGUAAUUUUAUGUAAUUAAAUGUACAUUUUUAAAUUUUUAGAUUACAUGUAAAUAUAACUUUUAAAAAAAUGUGUUAAGACCAUUGUACAUUCAAUGAAGCAUUAUUAUGCUUCUAACUUUAACCUAUUUCACCUUACUCAAGAGUGUAUGUAAAAGAUGGUAACAAUAUACUAUUUGGUAACAUAAUGGACUAACAUUUCUAUUAAUCUAUUUCACCAGUGGCUUUCAACUGCAAAUAAGUUAAAGAAUAUUUUUCUAUAGGUUAAAUAUUCUUUUUUGUCUUAUUUAAACUUACUGUUCUUAAUUUCUGUGGGUACAUAGUAUGAUUUUAAUUACCUUAUUUUAUUCUUUGUGCUAUUCAUAAUUUUUUUUGUUUGUUUGGUUUUUUUUUUUGAGACAGAGUCUUGCUCUCGCCCAGGCUGGAGUGCAGUGGCGCGAUCUUGGCUCACUGCAAGCUCCGCCUCCCAGGUUCACUCCAUUCUCCUGCCUCAGCCUCCCAAGUAGCUGGGACCACAGGCGCCCACUACUUGUUUGGGUUUUUUUUUGGAGAUGGAGUCUCGCUCUGUCACCCAGGCUGGAGUACAGUGGCAUGAUCUUGGCUCACUGCAACCCCCACCUCCCCGGUUCAAGUGAUUCUCCUGCCUCAGCCUCCCGAAUAGCUGGGAUUACAGGCGUCCACCAUCACACCAGGCUAAUUUUUGUAUUUUUAGUAGAGAUGGAGUUUCACCAUGUUGGCCAGGAUGGUCUCGAUCUUCUGACCUCAUGAUCUGCCUGCCUCGGCCUCCCAGAGUUCUGGGACCACAGGCAUGAGCCACUGCACCUGGCCAAAUGUGUAUAUAUUUAUGCAAUAUAUAACAUGUUUUGAUACAGGCAUAUAAUAUGUAUUAGUCACAUCAGGAUAAAGUAUCUAUUACCUUCAGCAUUUAUCCUUUGUAUUACAAGCCAAUUCUACACUUCAUUAUUUUAAUGUACAAUUAAAUUGUUAUUGACUACAGGGUCAUUUUAAUUAUAAAAAUUAUAUAGAAGUAUAAAUAAAGUCCAUACAUUCCUGAGUCAUGAAUAAA